AUGUGGAGGCUCACGGAGCGUCGGCGGAAGGCGCACAGGAUGCUAAAGCUUUACAACGGCCUCUCAGAAGGGGAAGCGGUGGGACUCCCUGCAGGGCCCGACCCCCUGGACCCCACUGAUCUGAACGGGGCACACUUUGACCCGGAAGUUUACCUAGACAAGCUGCCUAGAGAGUCCCCUCUGGCCCAGCUGAUGGACAGUGAGACGGACAUGGUGCAGCAGAUCCGGGCUCUAGACAGCGACAUGCAAACCCUGGUCUAUGAGAACUACGAUAAGUUCAUCCCAGCCACAGAAAUGACAAACAGCAUAAAACUACCUCCCAGUGCCAAGUCUAUAAACGUGUCUGGAAUUGGGAGACCAUCGGGGUGCAACCUGGUUGGGGCGGGGAGGAGGUGCAGGGCCUGGCCAGAGCGGGCAUGGCCGCAGGCAGGGGACAGCGACUGCUUGGGCCAGGGCAGGCGAGCUCAGCGCAGGCCAGGGCCCGGCGUGUCCGCGGUGGGCGCGAGCGGCCAGCAGAGGGCGCCAGAGAGCAACGAGCGGCCCGCGGAGGAGCCCACGCCCGCCCCGAUGCCUAGCUCCGCGCCGCGCGGACCCACCGAGCCCGCGCUCAGACGCCCCAGCUCCGCCGACAGGCCGCUCGCGCCGGGUCCUUCCUCUUCCCCAGGUGCAGGCAGAGCCCCCGGAGCCAUGGCCAGCCCUUCCGGCAGCUCCAAAGCCACUGGCAAGCCCCGAGGCAGGGAUGGCCGGCCCAGGAGAGAGGAGGACGACGUCACUCCCGAAGAGAAGAGGCUGCGGCUGUUGCUGGAGGAGGGAAGCGCACAGCCCGAUGACGGGGAGGACGCACCGCGGCCAGGCAGGAAGGAGACCGGCACCCAGACAGGUGGCGACGGCAGAGGAAGAAUUAUAAUGUGUUUCAACAAAGGCAGCCAUGGCUUUGAUAAUGUCCUCAUGGAUAUGAAGACCAUAUUCAGAGAUUUCGGGCCAGAUUUCAAGAGGAAUGGCCUGGCCGAGACUUUUAACAGCAUCCACAUCUACCCCUUCGUGUGUAAGCUCCUGGGAGUCACCCCCAAACCCACAACGGCUCCCUGGCAGUCACCCAGGAAAUGCUCGUGAACUCUUAUGACCAGCAGCCAGGUGAGACACAAAAGCAGCUGCCAGAAAACUGCCAGCAGAGUCUGCUCUGUCCUGAGAUAGAAAAGAAUCAAAAAGGGGUCUCAUGGUGGGGAGGAGGGAAUUCAAGCAGAACACUCCUGUUUCCCAGCAGCUUCGGAGCCCCAGGAACAUGAUGCCAACAGCUCCAAACAGAUAGCACGGGAGGUAGGGAAUCCCUCGACCUGCUGGUAACAUUUGACAUAGUGCCUUUUAGGCAAAGGGAAGGUGCUCUAUAGAGAAAGUCGGGCUGUAAUCCUUCCGGUCCUAAGGAAAUCACUGUGUACACUCUGCCCCCAAGAUGCCCCUUCCAGAUACGGAAAUCAGCCCUGCUUCAAUAGCACAAAAAACUCUUCAUAGGGGAGGAGCAAAACCCUGUUCACUCGAUGCUGAAAAAAGGAGACGGGAGAGUCUGAAACGAGACUGCAAAUUCUCAAGACUUCAAACCCCUUCGGUCUGGGUAAUACAAAGGAAGAAUAAAAUCAUCUCAGAA